GAGAAUUGCUCCUGCCCUGGGAAGAGGCUCAGCACAGAAAGAGGAAGGACAGCACAGCUGACAGCCGUGCUCAGAGAGUUUCUGGAUCCUAGGCUUAUCUCCACAGAGGAGAACACACAAGCAGCAGAGACCAUGGGAACCCUCUCAGCCCCUCCCUGCACACAGCGCAUCAAAUGGAAGGGGCUCCUGCUCACAGCAUCACUUUUAAACUUCUGGAACCUGCCCACCACUGCCCAAGUCACGAUUGAAGCCGAGCCAACCAAAGUUUCCGAGGGGAAGGAUGUUCUUCUACUUGUCCACAAUUUGCCCCAGAAUCUUACCGGCUACAUCUGGUACAAAGGGCAAAUGAGGGACCUCUACCAUUACAUUACAUCAUAUGUAGUAGACGGUGAAAUAAUUAUAUAUGGGCCUGCAUAUAGUGGACGAGAAACAGCAUAUUCCAAUGCAUCCCUGCUGAUCCAGAAUGUCACCCGGGAGGACGCAGGAUCCUACACCUUACACAUCAUAAAGGGAGAUGAUGGGACUAGAGGAGUAACUGGACGUUUCACCUUCACCUUACACCUGGAGACUCCUAAGCCCUCCAUCUCCAGCAGCAACUUAAAUCCCAGGGAGACCAUGGAGGCUGUGAGCUUAACCUGUGACCCUGAGACUCCAGACGCAAGCUACCUGUGGUGGAUGAAUGGUCAGAGCCUCCCUAUGACUCACAGCUUGAAGCUGUCCGAAACCAACAGGACCCUCUUUCUAUUGGGUGUCACAAAGUAUACUGCAGGACCCUAUGAAUGUGAAAUACGGAACCCAGUGAGUGCCAGCCGCAGUGACCCAGUCACCCUGAAUCUCCUCCCGAAGCUGCCCAAGCCCUACAUCACCAUCAACAACUUAAACCCCAGGGAGAAUAAGGAUGUCUUAAACUUCACCUGUGAACCUAAGAGUGAGAACUACACCUACAUUUGGUGGCUAAAUGGUCAGAGCCUCCCGGUCAGUCCCAGGGUAAAGCGACCCAUUGAAAACAGGAUCCUCAUUCUACCCAGUGUCACGAGAAAUGAAACAGGACCCUAUCAAUGUGAAAUACGGGACCGAUAUGGUGGCAUCCGCAGUGACCCAGUCACCCUGAAUGUCCUCUAUGGUCCAGACCUCCCCAGAAUUUACCCUUCAUUCACCUAUUACCGUUCAGGAGAAGUCCUCUACUUGUCCUGUUCUGCGGACUCUAACCCACCGGCACAGUAUUCUUGGACAAUUAAUGAAAAGUUUCAGCUACCAGGACAAAAGCUCUUUAUCCGCCAUAUUACUACAAAGCAUAGCGGGCUCUAUGUUUGCUCUGUUCGUAACUCAGCCACUGGCAAGGAAAGCUCCAAAUCCAUGACAGUCGAAGUCUCUGGUAAGUGGAUCCCAGCAUCGUUGGCAAUAGGGUUUUAGGUGGAGUCUAUCUGGCAUUCAGAGAAGAGUCAGGAAAACAAUUGUAUUCCCAGCCUGUGUCCCAUGGGCACAAGCAAAUCCCAAAUUCUCCUCCUGAACCCUCCAAAUUUGUCUAAGAACUUCGAAAACUUUAACAAACAGGCUGAUAUCUUCAUAAUAUUCCCAGCCUAGACCAAGCAGGAAGAACAUUGAUUUCAUUGAAAUAAUUGAUAAUAAUGAAGAUAAUGUUUUUAUGAUUUUUAUUUGAAAAUUUGCUGAUUCUUUAAAUGGUUUGUUUUCUACAUUGAUGGAAUUUUUCUCUUUUAAUCUAUCUACAGCUUAUAGCAGUUCAAUAAACUAUACUUCUGGGAACCGUAAUUGAAACAUUUACUUUUGCUUUCUACCUGACUGCCCCAGAAUUGGGCAACUAUUCAUGAGAAUUGAUAUGUUUAUGGUAAUACACAUAUUUGCACAAGUACAGUAACAAUCUGCUUUCUUUGUAACAUGACACAUUUGAAAUCAUUGGUUAUAUUACCAAUGCUUUGAUUCGGAUGUUAUAUUAAAAACAUAGAUAGAAUGAACCAAUAUGAACUGCAGGCAAAGUCUGAAGUCAGCCUUGGUUUGGCUUCCUAUUCUCAAGAGGUUUGUGAAGAUUUAAUCUCAGAUUCCUUAUAAAAACUUAGAGAAAAGAAAAUUUUAGAAGACAGCCUACAUGGUCCAUUGCUACUCUUGCUGCACUUAUGUAAACAAUCAGACCACAUUUGAAGAAACUCCACCUAUUUUGCAAACAAACUUAUUCUACUGAAAUUAUCAUUGGUAAAAGUAGAGAUGCCCAUAGAGGGAAAAAUUAUGUGGAAAAUAAAAACUGUAGUAUACCUGU